AUUUUGGAUGGUGAACCCUGAAGUCGGUGUCUGCUGCGUUCACGGCAGGAUUCGGUUAGGAGGAACAGCACAGCAUGCUGGGCUCUGGAUUUAAAGCUGAGCGCUUAAGAGUGAAUUUGAGAUUAGUCAUAAAUCGCCUUAAACUAUUGGAGAAAAAGAAAACGGAACUGGCCCAGAAAGCAAGGAAGGAGAUUGCUGACUAUCUGGCUGCUGGGAAAGAUGAACGAGCUCGGAUCCGUGUGGAGCACAUUAUCCGGGAAGACUACCUCGUGGAGGCCAUGGAGAUCCUGGAGCUGUACUGUGACCUGCUGCUGGCUCGGUUUGGCCUUAUCCAGUCUAUGAAGGAACUAGAUUCUGGUCUGGCUGAAUCUGUGUCUACAUUGAUCUGGGCUGCUCCUCGACUCCAGUCAGAAGUGGCUGAGUUGAAAAUAGUUGCUGAUCAGCUCUGUGCCAAGUAUAGCAAGGAAUAUGGCAAGCUAUGUAGGACCAACCAGAUUGGAACUGUGAAUGACAGGCUAAUGCACAAGCUGAGUGUGGAAGCCCCACCCAAAAUCCUGGUGGAGAGAUACCUGAUUGAAAUUGCAAAGAAUUACAACGUACCCUAUGAACCUGACUCUGUGGUCAUGGCAGAAGCUCCUCCUGGGGUAGAGACAGAUCUUAUUGAUGUUGGAUUCACAGAUGAUGUGAAGAAAGGAGGCCCUGGAAGAGGAGGGAGUGGUGGCUUCACAGCACCAGUUGGUGGACCUGAUGGAACGGUGCCAAUGCCCAUGCCCAUGCCCAUGCCUAUGCCAUCUGCAAAUACGCCUUUCUCAUAUCCACUGCCAAAGGGACCAUCAGAUUUCAAUGGACUGCCAAUGGGGACUUAUCAGGCCUUUCCCAAUAUUCAUCCACCUCAGAUACCAGCAACUCCCCCAUCGUAUGAAUCUGUAGAUGACAUUAAUGCUGAUAAGAAUAUCUCUUCUGCACAGAUUGUUGGUCCUGGACCCAAGCCAGAAGCCUCUGCAAAGCUUCCUUCCAGACCUGCAGAUAACUAUGACAACUUUGUCCUACCAGAGUUGCCAUCUGUGCCAGACACACUACCAACUGCAUCUGCUGGUGCCAGCACCUCAGCAUCUGAAGACAUUGACUUUGAUGAUCUUUCCCGGAGGUUUGAAGAGCUGAAAAAGAAAACAUAGGUCUCUUAAACCAGGCAACUUUCACGUUUUGGGAGUUGAGACUGAGCAAUUUCUCCUUGUAACAAAGAAUCUCCAUGAAAUUCUGUUUCAUCUGUUAACCGUCACUCAGCACAACACUCCCUCUGGGCUCUCUUCCUGCUCCUCCAGAUUCUGCUGCUUUCCAGUUCUCUGUUGAUCCUGAGACUAACAAUUGGAGACUGAGGCCAGAGCAACUGGCUCCUGGCAGCUGUGCUUGUCCGUUUCCUGUCAGAGUGAUCCCAGGUUUCCUCCUGGCCCGUCCCAUGGUCCCUCCACAGGAGUGUGAGAGGAUGGGGGAAGCACUGUGGGAAGACCACCAAAGAUGGCUGGACAGUGGGAGAGAGCACGUUGUGAAGCAUCCCAGCCUCGUGUUGAGGUUCCAGACUUAGAAACAGACCCCUCUGUACAGGGGGAUUGUGGUGAGUGAGAAUCAAGGCCACCUUGUGUGUUUUCUCACUCUCGAAUGCAAGUGGGAGAGGGAAAAUGACUCGGGACGCCAUUGUAACGGUUCCUGGAAGCUGGGCCCUCUCAUUGGCAUAUACAGUACUCCUCGCUGCAGGGCACUGUCCCACCGGGAUCCAGUUGCAAAGUUUGUCUUGACAGUUGAAGGCCUCGCUUAGUUGUACUGGAUUCUCAGGGAGCCCUCUGUGGCCUUUUGCUUUGCGUGCUGUUUCCCUUGUACCAGAGGGCGGCACCGUGGAAAUUCUGUUUUCCCUGUAGCAUAUUGUGUUGGAUUGCAUUACUGGCAGAGAAAGGACAAGGUGCCAUUCAAGUCCUAGGGUGGGCUUCCAGCUGCCUUAAUAGAAGUACUCAAGUCUUUUGGGUAGUGAGCUGGAAAGCCUACAGGAAAAGAGGGGUACCUGUUUUCAUUUGAAAACUUUGAUUCAUGGAACCUUUAAAACUAAUCUCAGAAAAAUUUUUGGUGCCCAUGCAGCUGUAGUUGUUCACUGCUUUCCUGGAUGGAUGGGACUCUUAUGUCAUAACUUCUGUUACUCCUUUGGCCCAUAGCUAAGGUCAUCCUUCCCCACAGGGGUGGCUUUGGGAUUGGAUGAUACAGCUUUUGCUUCUGUGUAGUAUACCUGUACAUACUUGUUUCAGGCAGCCUUUCUUUAAUGUUUUCAGUUGGUUUGUAUUCUGUAGCUCAGUAGCUGCUAAUAAAGUUAAAGAUCCUGUGUCCUGCUUUCUCUACUGUUUGGUCAGAUGAUGAAGUAUAAAUCUGGAUUUUAGUGGAGAAUAUUUUAACCAAGUGAUCCAUGUAAACCAGCCCUUAGUUUCAGGAUUCCUGGAGCAGUACAGAGCUCAUUUUGAUCUCUGUAUUUAGAUAGCCCAGAUAGCAUCUGUGAAUUUCCUUGGUCUUCCUCAGUGGCAGGGCUCCGCAUCUGCCAUGCCUCAUCCUUGGAUGUUUAUUUUUAGUAAGUUGCAGUGAGCUCACUUCUGACUGCUUCAUUUCCCGCAGCCAUCCUGGGCCAUGGGUGGUGAGUUCUGUUACUUGCUGCUUGGCAGCAGAGCUAGUUUGUCUCGUAGUAUUCUUGCAUUGUUAAUCCUAUCUUGACAGUGCCAAGAUCCAUAAGAACUUGGGACCAAGGGGAUUUUGAUUCCUAACUUACAGAAUUAAAAACAAAGUAUAUUAUAAUUUUAAAGCUAUGCCAUGCAAAGAUAAGUAGUAAUACGCUAAUAAAUACUAAGCCAAGUAGGAGAUAACAGGAUUAAGGUAGUUCAUCUAAAACUUCAGUGUCACUGCCCACUGCUGUCGUGGCUGCUUGCUCAGAUGAGGUUUUUUGGGGCCAACUGAUUCCUAACAAAUUUGAGAGCUUCUGUAGCAGUGUAUCUAUUAGUGCAGCUUCUUUCUGAGUAUUGAAGACAAAAAGAGAAAAGUGAGAAAAUUGAAAUUACUGCUAAUAGUGGAGUAAAAAAAGUACCAAAGAUUUUUAAAAAAUUAGUAAAUGUAAAGAUACUAUUUCUUUAAUAAUUUGCAGUCAGGCAUUGGAGUGUUUCCACUAAUGGUUGCGAGCCAACUAUUUAUAGGACAAUGGCUAUAGAAUAUUAUGUAGUCUUAUAAAUUGGGUUUCCUAGGAAGAUAGCUGGCAGAGCUUUUGAAACUAAUAAAGGGAAUAUGAUACUGUGCAUUAUAAAUUAUGUCAGCCCGUCAUCUUAGGGGCAGUUACAGUGGAGCUUUCCCAGUGAUAUAACAGCAUGCUAGUUUAUCUUUUAGUUACCUACCUUAAGCGACUUUCUUUCUUUUCCAAAGGCCAUGAGAAUGGCCGAAACGAAAAGAUUAAUUACCACAAGUACCAUCAAGAUGACACUGGUGAGGAUCAGAAAGGUGCCCAGGACUGGGUCUAAAGCGAAAACCUGGGAAAACAAUAAGAACACUUGCAGUGACUGACAAUUUAGUUUAUACUUUACAAACAUAAGCUAUAUGCUAGUGUUUGGGAUCUUAUCAGAAGAAAAGCUUAUCCGAAGGAAACUUAGGGAGAGAGUCAAAAGAUAAUAAGAAGGAAAAUACUUUUAAAUGGACAGAAGAGCAGGAAUGACUCAUUUUAAGGAGGUUAAGAUAAUUGUGACUGCAGGGCUUUCACAAGAAAACAGGUGAGUUGCAGUGGAAUUGGAAAUGAUUCAAAUGUCACAUGAGUUUUGGCAAAAAAUACAUCUAAUCAUGGAAGCUAAAAGUGGGAGGGGGGUAAGCAAACACUGAAAGAUUAAAUGCAUACCAGAAAUGAGAAUGCACACUGUCUCUGCCAUAUCAAGAAACUACAACCCUAAACACAGGAGCAUUCCAAUAAAAGUUAACAGGUUGGCCACAGAAAACUGGCUUUUUAGUAUUUUUUUUUUUCCAUUGUCAUUUUUAAAGGUACAAGCAUUGAGUUCUGCCAUUCUUUACUUUUCUGCAUACAUAAAUAUCAAGUUCUGGGCUUAUUGGAAUGGUUCCCAUAACAAAAACUGUUGUUUAAAAUUUAGAUGUUCUUUUUCAACAAAUGGUAUUUAUUUUCCCUUGGUAUUGGCCCAUUCAUUGUUGCCACUAGGGCACUGUUUAAAAAUAUCCCAACAGAGGGGUUGAUUACAGUCAAUGCCACCCUGAUGGAAAUCUAUAUGGCAAAAUAUUUUCAAGCACCAAACUGUUUUACCUACUUAAAAAUGAUUAUUAUAACAAUUUCAGGUCAACCAGAUAAUGUGGGCAAUCUCUGAGUUUGUGAUACAAGACUUAUUUCCAAUAAGUUUAUUUUUAUGUACAAUUUUACUGUUUAUUUUUUGUUUGCUCUAUUUGUUUUUUAAUGUUUUUUACUUUAUGUUUACUGUAUUUUUAUGUACAAUUACAUCCAAAGCAGAAAAGUUCCUUUUUUAUCCCCAAAAGGAGGUGUCAGCAAAAA